AGGUGCGGGGAGGAAAGGAGAGGGUGCUCAGGCAGCGAGAACAGGGCGCAGCUAACGCCGGGGAGGAGGAUCCCGUCCUCAUGGGUGCGGGAGCAACGUGGCGUGGGAGUGAUCGUUCUGGGGGAGAGUGGGCAGAAGAGAGCGCGAGGCGAGCCCGGGGCCAGGGGCGCAGGGAAUAGUGGCUUUGGAGCUAGCGCUCUGCCGACCAGACAGUAGGACACAUGCUGGUUUCGCCUACUGAGAUGGCUUCCCACCCGUAACCUGCUUGGAGAUUCUUGACACUGCCUGCCCCUCUGACAUCGCUGCCCUGAGAUGGCUCUAUAGAGCCAGAGGACUGGACAGGACCUGCCUCCCGCUCGUUUGGUUCCGGCCUCAGGCUUAGGACAAUGGGGUGUUCCUAGCACCCGAGCGGGCCUCCUGGUCACAGUGCGCCUUUUAGGUGGCUCUCCCAGCGUCUUCACUGACUUUCGUGAAAUAGUGUCCUGCGCCCUAGUGAAACUACCCUGCCUUCACUUAGGCCCGUUUUCUUGAGGAGUGAAGCUGUCGGCCGCUGUGGCCCCUCCUGUGCCGCAGGCGCAUGCGAAACAGGGACCGAACGAGCCCCGCCUCGACGCCUCCAAUCCCACUGAUCCCCCUGCCUCGGCCCUCGUUCCGAGAACGACCGUUCCAUUCAUUCAGUCUUGGCAGUAGUUAUUUGAUUCGUCUUCUCUUGUAGUAUACUUUAAAGUGUGGGCGAUGCAGUUGGCUGUGGUGCUUUAAUAAAGAUCUGAUCGAUGCGGAGUUUGGUAGAUGUAUAUUACAGUUCUCGAACGUGUUGCUUGUUUUGGCACACUGCACAGUCAUUUUUCAUGUGGAUUUGUGACUUUGUCGUGGACCAGGGAAAUAAGUCCUGUGGUGUGGGAGUCGUAGGUUUAGUUGUUAUCUUCGACUCGUGCUGUCCCUUUUUCAGGAAUGUAAGAAGCACUUGGCAGGCUUGGGGGCUUUGGGGCUGGGCAGCCUGAUCACUGAACUCACGGCAAAUGAAGAAUUGACCGGGACUGACGGUGCCUUGGGUGGGUUAGGAGUACAGAAGAUGCUGUGGACUAUUCAGACAUCAAUGAGGUGGCAGAAGAUGAAAGCCGAAGAUACCAGCAGACGAUGGGGAGCUUGCAGCCCCUUUGCCACUCAGAUUAUGAUGAAGAUGACUAUGAUGCUGAUUGUGAAGACAUUGAUUGCAAGUUGAUGCCUCCUCCACCUCCACCCCCGGGACCAAUGAAGAAGGAUAAGGACCAGGAUUCUAUUACUGGUGUGUCUGAAAAUGGAGAAGGCAUCAUCUUGCCCUCCAUCAUUGCCCCUUCCUCUUUGGCCUCAGAGAAAGUGGACUUCAGUAGUUCCUCUGACUCAGAAUCUGAGAUGGGACCUCAGGAAGCAACACAGGCAGAAUCUGAAGAUGGAAAGCUGACCCUUCCAUUGGCUGGGAUUAUGCAGCAUGAUGCCACCAAGCUGUUGCCAAGUGUCACAGAACUUUUUCCAGAAUUUCGACCUGGAAAGGUGUUACGUUUUCUACGUCUUUUUGGACCAGGGAAGAAUGUCCCAUCUGUUUGGCGGAGUGCUCGGAGAAAGAGGAAGAAGAAGCACCGUGAGCUGAUACAGGAAGAGCAGAUCCAGGAGGUGGAGUGCUCAGUAGAAUCAGAAGUCAGCCAGAAGUCUUUGUGGAACUACGACUACGCUCCACCACCACCUCCAGAGCAGUGUCUCUCUGAUGAUGAAAUCACGAUGAUGGCUCCUGUGGAGUCCAAAUUUUCCCAAUCAACUGGAGAUAUAGAUAAAGUGACAGAUACCAAACCAAGAGUGGCUGAGUGGCGUUAUGGGCCUGCCCGACUGUGGUAUGAUAUGCUGGGUGUCCCUGAAGAUGGCAGUGGGUUUGACUAUGGCUUCAAACUGAGAAAGACAGAACAUGAACCUGUGAUAAAAUCUAGAAUGAUAGAGGAAUUUAGGAAACUUGAGGAAAACAAUGGCACUGAUCUUCUGGCUGAUGAAAACUUCCUGAUGGUGACACAGCUGCAUUGGGAGGAUGAUAUCAUCUGGGAUGGGGAGGAUGUCAAACACAAAGGGACAAAACCUCAGCGUGCAAGCCUGGCAGGCUGGCUUCCUUCUAGCAUGACUAGGAAUGCGAUGGCUUACAAUGUUCAGCAAGGUUUUGCAGCCACUCUUGAUGAUGACAAACCUUGGUACUCCAUUUUUCCCAUUGACAAUGAGGAUCUGGUAUAUGGACGCUGGGAGGACAAUAUCAUUUGGGAUGCUCAGGCCAUGCCCCGGCUGUUGGAACCUCCUGUUUUGACACUUGAUCCCAAUGAUGAGAACCUCAUUUUGGAAAUUCCUGAUGAGAAGGAAGAGGCCACCUCUAACUCCCCCUCCAAGGAGAGUAAGAAGGAAUCAUCUCUGAAGAAGAGUCGAAUUCUCUUAGGGAAAACAGGAGUCAUCAAGGAGGAACCACAGCAGAACAUGUCUCAGCCAGAAGUGAAAGAUCCAUGGAAUCUCUCCAAUGAUGAGUAUUAUUAUCCCAAGCAACAGGGUCUUCGAGGCACCUUUGGAGGGAAUAUUAUCCAGCAUUCAAUUCCUGCUGUGGAAUUACGGCAGCCCUUCUUUCCCACCCACAUGGGGCCCAUCAAACUCCGGCAGUUCCAUCGCCCACCUCUGAAAAAGUACUCAUUUGGUGCACUUUCUCAGCCAGGUCCCCACUCAGUCCAACCUUUGCUAAAGCACAUCAAAAAAAAGGCCAAGAUGAGAGAACAAGAGAGGCAAGCUUCAGGUGGUGGAGAGAUGUUUUUUAUGCGCACACCUCAGGACCUCACAGGCAAAGAUGGUGAUCUUAUUCUUGCAGAAUAUAGUGAGGAAAAUGGACCCUUAAUGAUGCAGGUUGGCAUGGCAACCAAGAUAAAGAACUAUUAUAAACGGAAACCUGGAAAAGAUCCUGGAGCACCAGAUUGUAAAUAUGGGGAAACUGUUUACUGCCAUACAUCUCCUUUCCUGGGUUCUCUCCAUCCUGGCCAAUUGCUGCAAGCAUUUGAGAACAACCUUUUUCGUGCUCCAAUUUAUCUUCAUAAGAUGCCAGAAACUGAUUUCUUGAUCAUUCGGACAAGACAGGGUUACUAUAUUCGGGAAUUAGUGGAUAUUUUUGUGGUUGGCCAGCAGUGUCCCUUGUUUGAAGUUCCUGGGCCUAACUCCAAAAGGGCCAAUACGCAUAUUCGAGACUUUCUACAGGUUUUUAUUUACCGCCUUUUCUGGAAAAGUAAAGAUCGGCCACGGAGGAUACGAAUGGAAGAUAUAAAAAAAGCCUUUCCUUCCCAUUCAGAAAGCAGCAUCCGGAAGAGGCUAAAGCUCUGCGCUGACUUCAAACGCACAGGGAUGGACUCAAACUGGUGGGUGCUUAAGUCUGAUUUUCGUUUACCAACGGAAGAAGAGAUCAGAGCUAUGGUGUCACCAGAGCAGUGCUGUGCUUAUUAUAGCAUGAUAGCUGCAGAGCAACGACUGAAGGAUGCUGGCUAUGGUGAGAAAUCCUUUUUUGCUCCAGAAGAAGAAAAUGAGGAAGAUUUCCAGAUGAAGAUUGAUGAUGAAGUUCGCACUGCCCCUUGGAACACCACAAGGGCCUUCAUUGCUGCCAUGAAGGGCAAGUGUCUGCUAGAGGUGACUGGGGUGGCAGAUCCCACGGGGUGUGGUGAAGGAUUCUCCUAUGUGAAGAUUCCAAACAAACCAACACAGCAGAAGGAUGAUAAAGAACCGCAGCCAGUGAAGAAGACAGUGACAGGAACAGAUGCAGACCUUCGUCGCCUUUCCCUGAAAAAUGCCAAGCAACUUCUACGUAAAUUUGGUGUGCCUGAGGAAGAGAUUAAAAAGUUGUCCCGCUGGGAAGUGAUUGAUGUGGUGCGCACAAUGUCAACAGAACAGGCUCGUUCUGGAGAGGGGCCCAUGAGUAAAUUUGCCCGUGGAUCAAGGUUUUCUGUGGCUGAGCAUCAAGAGCGUUACAAAGAGGAAUGUCAGCGCAUCUUUGACCUACAGAACAAGGUUCUGUCAUCAACUGAAGUCUUAUCAACUGACACAGACAGCAGCUCAGCUGAAGAUAGUGACUUUGAAGAAAUGGGAAAGAACAUUGAGAACAUGUUGCAGAACAAGAAAACCAGCUCUCAGCUUUCACGUGAACGGGAGGAACAGGAGCGGAAGGAACUACAGCGAAUGCUACUGGCAGCAGGCUCAGCAGCAUCCGGAAACAAUCACAGAGAUGAUGACACAGCUUCCGUGACUAGCCUUAACUCUUCUGCCACUGGACGCUGUCUCAAGAUUUAUCGCACGUUUCGAGAUGAAGAGGGGAAAGAGUAUGUUCGCUGUGAGACAGUCCGAAAACCAGCUGUCAUUGAUGCCUAUGUGCGCAUACGGACUACAAAAGAUGAGGAAUUCAUUCGAAAAUUUGCCCUUUUUGAUGAACAACAUCGGGAAGAGAUGCGAAAAGAACGGCGGAGGAUUCAAGAGCAACUGAGGCGGCUUAAGAGGAACCAGGAAAAGGAGAAGCUUAAGGGUCCUCCUGAGAAGAAGCCCAAGAAAAUGAAGGAGCGUCCUGACCUAAAACUGAAAUGUGGGGCAUGUGGUGCCAUUGGACACAUGAGGACUAACAAAUUCUGCCCCCUCUAUUAUCAAACAAAUGCGCCACCUUCCAACCCUGUUGCCAUGACAGAAGAACAGGAGGAGGAGUUGGAAAAGACAGUCAUUCAUAAUGAUAAUGAAGAACUUAUCAAGGUUGAAGGGACCAAAAUUGUCUUGGGGAAACAGCUAAUUGAGAGUGCGGAUGAGGUUCGCAGAAAAUCUCUGGUUCUCAAGUUUCCUAAACAGCAGCUUCCUCCAAAGAAGAAACGGCGAGUUGGAACCACUGUUCACUGUGACUAUUUGAAUAGACCUCAUAAGUCCAUCCACCGGCGCCGCACAGACCCUAUGGUGACGCUGUCGUCCAUCUUGGAGUCUAUCAUCAAUGACAUGAGAGAUCUUCCAAAUACAUACCCUUUCCACACUCCAGUCAAUGCAAAGGUUGUAAAGGACUACUACAAAAUCAUCACUCGGCCAAUGGACCUACAAACACUCCGCGAAAACGUGCGUAAACGCCUCUACCCAUCUCGGGAAGAGUUCAGAGAGCAUCUGGAGCUAAUUGUGAAAAAUAGUGCAACCUACAAUGGGCCAAAACACUCAUUGACUCAGAUCUCUCAAUCCAUGCUGGAUCUCUGUGAUGAAAAACUCAAAGAGAAAGAAGACAAAUUAGCUCGCUUAGAGAAAGCUAUCAACCCCUUGCUGGAUGAUGAUGACCAAGUGGCGUUUUCUUUCAUUCUGGACAACAUUGUCACCCAGAAAAUGAUGGCAGUUCCAGAUUCUUGGCCAUUUCAUCACCCAGUUAAUAAGAAAUUUGUUCCAGAUUAUUACAAAGUGAUUGUCAAUCCAAUGGAUUUAGAGACCAUACGUAAGAACAUCUCCAAGCACAAGUAUCAGAGUCGGGAGAGCUUUCUGGAUGAUGUAAACCUUAUUCUGGCCAACAGUGUUAAGUAUAAUGGACCUGAGAGUCAGUAUACUAAGACUGCCCAGGAGAUUGUGAACGUCUGUUACCAGACAUUGACUGAGUAUGAUGAACAUUUGACUCAACUUGAGAAGGAUAUUUGUACUGCUAAAGAAGCAGCUUUGGAGGAAGCAGAAUUAGAAAGCCUGGACCCAAUGACCCCAGGGCCCUACACGCCUCAGCCUCCUGAUUUGUAUGAUACCAACACAUCCCUCAGUAUGUCUCGAGAUGCCUCUGUAUUUCAAGAUGAGAGCAAUAUGUCUGUCUUGGAUAUUCCCAGUGCCACUCCAGAAAAGCAGGUAACACAGAUGCGCCAGGGCCGAGGUAGGCUGGGCGAGGAAGACUCUGAUGUAGAUAUUGAAGGGUAUGAUGAUGAGGAGGAGGAUGGGAAACCUAAGACUCCAGCCCCAGAAGGUGAAGAUGGAGAUGGUGAUCUUGCAGAUGAAGAGGAAGGAACUGUACAACAGCCUCAAGCCAGUGUCCUGUAUGAGGAUUUGCUUAUGUCUGAAGGAGAAGAUGAUGAGGAAGAUGCUGGGAGUGAUGAAGAAGGAGACAAUCCUUUCUCUGCUAUCCAGCUGAGUGAAAGUGGAAGUGACUCUGAUGUGGGAUCUGGUGGAAUAAGACCCAAACAACCCCGCAUGCUUCAGGAGAACACAAGGAUGGACAUGGAAAAUGAAGAAAGCAUGAUGUCCUAUGAGGGAGACGGUGGGGAGGCUUCCCAUGGUUUGGAGGAUAGCAACAUCAGUUAUGGGAGCUAUGAGGAGCCUGAUCCCAAGUCGAACACCCAAGACACAAGCUUCAGCAGCAUCGGUGGGUAUGAGGUAUCAGAGGAGGAAGAAGAUGAGGAGGAGGAAGAGCAGCGCUCUGGGCCGAGCGUACUAAGCCAGGUCCACCUGUCAGAGGACGAGGAGGACAGUGAGGAUUUCCACUCCAUUGCUGGGGACAGUGACUUGGACUCUGAUGAAUGAGGCUUCCUUUGGGCCUCCUUGGUCAGCCUUCCCUGUUCUCCAGCCUAGGUGGUUCACCUUUCCCCAAUUUGUUCAUAUUUGUACAGUAUCUGAUCCUGAAAUCAUGAAAUUAACUAACACCUUAGCCUUUUUAAAAGUAGUAAGUAAAUGAUAAUAAAUCACCUCUCCUAAUCUUCCUGGGGCAAUGUCACCCUUUGAUUUAAAACAAAGCAACCCCCUUUCCCCUACCACUACGGAAAAGAGCAAGCUCAUUUUUCCGUGUCCUCCUUUAUUUAACUCCAUUUAUUGCUUUUGGUAUAAUUUUUCCCUGGGGAAGGAGGGGAAAUUAUGAAAGAACUAGUAACUUUAUGUCCUCUUGAUGUAUUAGGAAAUUUCCGGCCAGGCGUGGUGGCUCACACCUGUAAUCUCAGCACUCUGGGAGGCCGAGGCGGGCAGAUCACCUGAGGUCAGAAGUUCGAGACCAGCUUGGCCAACAUGGCGAAACCGCAUCUCUACUAAAAAUACAAAAAUUAGCCAGGCUGGAGCAGAUGAGAGCCCUCCUGCUGGGACAGAGAAUUGGGUUCUAGUGGACUCUGUGCUACACUUAAACCUGUGAGACAAACCGCCCAUUAUUUUAUUAUUUAAUUAUGCAAUGCCUAGUUCCUAAAUGGAUUGGAGGCAAAUUACCGUAAAUUUUGAAACAGCCUAUAUGUCAGAAAUGAUAAUGUUGCCACCUAAAUGUUUUCUGUCCCCCCCACCCUCCCCAGGGGAAAUGGUAGGAAAAUGGUAAGUUUCUUAGGGCAAAGACUGUGUCUUCUGUUUCUUUUCAUGCUUAGGAUAUGGUUCUGUGCAUAGUAGGUACUCAGUAAAUGUUCCUAGAAUCAUAAAAUCCUCAACAGAUAUGUUACUGAGCAUCUGCUUUUCAUGAUAAGCACUCUAUCAGAUCCUUGGGAUGCAAAGGUAAAUAAGACAAAUCCCUUUUACCCAAAGAGCUCACCAUCAAGUUGGGGGAGGGAAAGUGGAAUUCAAAACAUGUUAAUAAAUCAUCAUAGUACUGUGAGAUAAGUGCAAUUAAGAAGCUAGUUAUAAAGUAUAGGGGAAAUAGAGGAGUAAUCAUGUCUGAAAAGUCAGGAAAGUCUUCCUAGAGGUAAUUUUUAAGCUGAUUGUUUUAGAAUUAGUAGAAGCUUGCCAGAUGGAAAAGUCCAGGCAAAGUGUAACAUGAAUGGGAAAGGCCACAGUCUAGAAAUGGCAGAGUGUGUUCCUAGUUUGUUUGUUUGUUUGUUUGUACCUGCCUUGUUCCAGGAAGGAUUUAAUGUGGUUUAUAUUCCAGUCCUUUAAUGCUGGAAGGGCUGAGAUGAGACUGAAAGAUGGGCAGGAAGUAUAUCAUCACAAGCUUUGUGUUUGAUGUUAAUGUGUAUGAUUUUUAUAUUAUGGGAAAUAAGCUCUUAGAGGAGUGAUAUAAUCAGGUUUGUGUUUUAGAAAUCUGUGUAAUGAAUGAAUGAAGAAAGAAAUUGAAGAAUCAUGUAACAUAUGUGAUCGCAUUUUUGUAAAAGAACCAUGUGUGUUUAUAUGUGUUUAUAUAUAUACUUGUGUAUGCAAAGGUAAAAGUCUGAAAGGAUAUAUGCUAACUGUUCACAAUGAUAACCCCCCAGGAAUGGGAUUGGAGGGGAGGGGGCUUCUGUGUUUGUUAUGUAUGCUGGGUGGGAUAUUGUGCUUUUAUUUCUAUAUUGUUUGAAUUUUUUUACAGUAUGUAUUAUUUUUGUAAUAAAAAUUUUAAAAAAUUCCA